UCGUGUUACUCCCUGGCUUUCAAGAGUCUCCACAGCUGACCACAGUUGUCCAUAGUUGUCCACAGCUAUUCAUGGCCCUGGGGCUUACAUCCUUGCUCCCUUCUGUGGUGUUCACAGCCUUUCCUUCCCACUCUGGCCCCAGCCUGUCUGCCCAGCCUCUAACCAUGGUGGCUUUUCCCCCACCAUUAUACUUGGACCUCAGACCACCUGUAGUGUCCCUCAGUCAGUCAACAACUGACCCCCCAAUUCAUCCCCCCAGUUCUCUCUCUUUCUCUCUUUCUUUAUCUUUCUCCCCACUACCCCUGUACUGUGUGCCCUGGGGCUCAGCCAUAGGCAGCAUAGAGCUGCCCUGCUCUGUGGCCUUGGCCUUCCAGGGUGGAAGCAGGAAACCCAAUUUAGUUUUGAUAGUCCUGAGAGUAGAGAGUGAGAAGAACAGCAUUUAGGGGAGGGAACAACCUGUGGGAAGGCCCUGAGGCAAACUUGGGAGGAAGAUUUGUAUUUUUAGGGUUGUGGGAAACCCUUGCAGAGGUUUAAGCCAAGGAAUGACUUGGCCGAUUGGGCUUGUAUUUUCAAUACUGCAGGUGGUAAUGGAGAACGUGUUAGCAGCAGGGGCUGAGAGAAGGGAGUGGAAGGAGAAGGGUCAGGCCUUAGUUGCUGAUUGGACCUACAGGGUAAGAUGAGAGAAGGAUGGAGGACACCUUGCAGGUCUCUGGAUUCAAAAUCUGGGUGGAUAAGGGUGUUCUGAGCCUGAGCCUCAGGAGGAGAGGGGCUGAGAGUGGAAAGAGCAAGUCCUCUGGCUGCCAGGGCUCACAUCCCAGCCCCUGCAGUUGUUGCUGUCAAUCCCUGACCCUCACUAUCCUCAUCUGUAAGAUGGGGAUUAAUGUAGUGCCCUUGCAGGGUCCUGCGAAUGUGGACGAUGCUGACAGCAGUCAGGGGGCUGCACCUAGUGGGUGCUGGGCAGGGGCACAUCUUUCCCUUCUUGUGCCAAGAAGCCACCCUCCAUUCCCCCAGAGCUAGUUUCUCUGUUGGAAUUGCCUUCCCAGCCAUCAUAGUUUCUGAUUUCUCCUCUUGUCAGGCUUUGCUUUUGUUUCCCUACUGGAUUCUGAGCCCCUUGGAACUCCAAUUCUAGGUAGUAAAGCCUAGACAUCUGCAUUUCUGAGCAAUUCCCCAGGUGAACUCAGCUGCUUAGAACAUUCUGCAUCCCUGUAGGGCUGGAGCUGUGUCUUCUUAGAGCCAGACACAUACGCAACCCUGGAAUGAAUGAACCACUAACAACCGUAUGGUCUCACAUCUCCCACAGAUAAACCCAGCAGGCUGGACUGCUCCAGUUUCGAGAGCAGCCCAGUCACCUGGGAGGGAUUUUAAUUUUAUUAUAUUUUUUUCUUAUUUGUUUAUUUAUUGGAGUCAGGGUCUCACUCUGUCGCCCAGGCUGGAGUGCAGUGGCCCAAUCAUAGCCUACGGCAACCUCGGACUCCUGGGUUCAAGCAGUCCUCCCACUUCAGCCUCCUGAGUAGCUGAGACUACAGGCAUGCAUCACCAUACCUGGCUAAUUUUUUAGUUUUUGUAGAGAUGGGGUCUCACUAUGUUGCUCAGGCUGGUCUCGAACUUCUGGCCUGAAGUGAUCCUCCUGCCUCAGCUUCCCAAAGUGCUGGGAUUACAGGCAUAAGCCACCGUGCCCGGCUCCUGGGAGGGAUCUUUAAAGUUCAGAUUCCCAGACCCAGCCUUGGCAAGUCUGUUUCAGAAGGUCUGAGCUGAGCAGAGCAUGAUUCUCUGCUUGGAUGAUUCUACCCAGCCAUGUCAGAACACCUGUAGGCUCUUAACGCUGUGUGUCCUCCUAGCUCUGACAUCCUCGUCCUCAGCCACAGGCCCUGGCAUGUCCUGCCAUGCUGGGUGAAGUUGGUUUUCUUGGUGCCAGGUCACCAGGUGGGGUUUCUGGGUAGUGGCAAUGGCUGUUCCCCUCCUGCAAUUAGCAGGAGUUAAAAUGUCUGGGUUCUGAACUUGUGUGUCUCUGCUGCCACCAGUAAUUACACAAGGUCAAGUAGGUUUAUGAUAGCUGAAAUUCUAACAGUUUGGGGGCCUGUGUCCCCAAUUCGCUUUGGUUUGUGGUCUCAUUCUCCCAGCCAGCCUUAAGGAGGAGGGGGGCGUGGGGCACAGCUGCUCCUACCCCGAGAGCACACAGAGCUCAAGUGCCAGGCUUUGCCUCCGGAAGCAUCUGUCUAUUUCCAUUGUCUGCCUCUCCUUGGACACAGAAGAAUGAUUAUAACCAAAUGGAGGGGUCCUCCUUCACCCGAUCUCCCUGCACAUUUCCAGAUGGCUUUUGUAGAAGUUGUAGUCUUGCUCUUGAUGUGCAAAUCUGUUGGGUAAUAGAGGUCUCAUCGUGCUGGAAGAAGUGCCUCCCCAGUUAAUUCUCCUCCACCCAAGCAGUCAGUGAAGGUUCAGCAGCUGGCAGAAUGGAAAUUGAUGGUGGACAUGUGACUUGACUGGCUGAGCUCCAUAAUGCUCAUUCCUCAUUGUCAUUUCUCAUGUGCACUGUGGGUGUGUGUCUCUUGGACAAGAGGAUUGUGGUCUGGAAUCCUGGAGGGAUCUUGCAAAGCAGAUCCAGAUCUUGGUGUAUGGAGUUAGGGCGGGGUGGUGGUGGUGCUGGAUGGAGUGGGAGGGAAGACCUGGAUCCUCUGAAGGCCAGCGCGUGUCUGGGCCAGCAGGAAGGGGCUGAAGUGCGUGAAGGCUCAUCCAAGGGUUACUAUCAGUCAGGUCACUUUCUCUGUGACUGUGGCUGAGCUUUACUGCCUCUGGAGAUCCACAUGCCUGUACAAUCUUGCCUUCUGGGUGGGUCUGUAAUUGUUCCUCAUGGGUAUUUUAGUAAUGUCUGGAUGUAUCUUUCCCCCACUUCUUCUCACCCUCCUGUUUGCUCAAGCAUCCCAGCUCCGGAAGGCUUCAGAUUCUAUCUCCUGCUCCUUUAACCCAGCUGCCCUGGGUUCACUUCAUUCCAACAGAGGUCUCCUCUCUUACAUCCAGCUCCCAAAAUCGACAGCAUUGAAUACAACGCUGACUCUGAAACUUGCUCACUGGGGGAUCUCCAAAAGGCUUUUUAACUUCUCCAAGAGACCCUCUGCUUUCCCAUCUUUUUUGGUUUGUUUUUAUAAAGGAGGAAAGGACACUGACCUUUGCAUGGCACUGUGCUGGGCUCUUUGCUUACACUGCUUCAUUGGAUCUCCAUAAUAGUCCCAUGAGAUGGACACCAUUACGACCCCUGCUUUCUAGUUGGGGAAACUGAGGCAUAGAGCAGUCCUUUCCAAGAUCUUAUAGCUGCUAAGUAGCAGAGGUCGAAUGAAUUUAAGUCCCAAUAGUUUCACUUUGUUGUUGUUGUUGUUUUUGAGACGAAGUUUUUUUUUUGUUUGUUUUUGUUUUUGUUUCUGUUUGAGACGGAGUCUUACUUAUUCUGUCACCCAGGCUGAAGUGCAGUGGCAAAAUCUCGGCUCACUGCAGCCUCCACCUCCCGGUUCAAGUGAUUCCCCUGCCUCAGCCUCCUGAGUAGCUGGGAUUCCAGGCUCAUGCUACCACGCCCAGCUAAUUUUUGUAGUUUUAGUGGAGACGGGGUUUCACCAUGUUGGCCAGAUUGGGCUUGAACUCCUGACCUCAGGUGAUCUGCCCACCUUGGCUCCCAAAGUGCUGGGAUUACAGGCGUUAGCCACCACACCAGGUCCCAGUAGUCUAAUUUUGGAACCCCAGGCCUCCAUUGGCUUUCUCUGUUGUAAAUGUUUUUGCAAUAUAGAUGUUUUAAUAGCUUAUGUAAAAUCUUGUCAUUGUGUAAUUAUGGUAUUAUGGAAUCACAUUUCUCUUGCAUUUAGUUCAUGUAAACGAAACUAGAAUCUCUUAGGAAAAAAAGAGAAAAACAGCAGUUUAAUCUCACUGUUCCACUUAAUGAGUGUAUAUUCUGAAGGAUACAGGAGAUUGGGGGUGGUGAAUCUGCUGGACUCCCUGUACAGGCCCCACAUUCGGAGCACUUCAACCAGGGCAGCUCUGUGUGUGAGUCUGGGGGUUAGAGGUGUGUGUUUUCCUUUGGCUCUGACCACCAACUUUACCUGCAGUGCAGCUGAACACACAGUCACCUGCUCUAGCACUGUAGGAGAACCGAGUUGUGUUCCUCCAGAGAGGGUGAGCAGCUCACUAAGAUGCAUCUUCCUGAGGGGUUUUCCAGGGGAAUUUUGAACUCUGCAGGAUUUUCCCACUAACUUUAGAAUUCGCCCUCCAGUGUCAGAAGGCUGAGCUUCGUCCUCCCUUUUGCAGGGUCUUUCUCAGCUGACAUUUGGGUCAGAGCACAGAGAUGGAGCUAAGAUUGAGCCAGAGAGUUUUGUUUUGUAGGGGAGUUGGGCUGCAUAUUUACUCAGGUGCCAGAACCUAUGAGAUAUUGGAAGUUUGGGAGGUCUGGACCCGGGAGUCAGACAGACCCAGCUGUUCAACCCCUAUUGUCCGGUUCCAACUGCUGGACCUUGGCCAGGUUGCUUAAAGCUGUAGUUUAUUUCGUUCUCGAAAAUGUGGAUAACAAUGUGCACAUCUCUGGGAUCUUGUGUGAAUUUGCAGUUAGAGAACAGGUCCUUGAUAUAUCUUGGUCAUCUGUGCCCCUUAACUAGAGCCUCAUAGAUUUCAGUGAAUUGUAAAUUGUCUCUAAGUGGCUAGCUAGGUAUAAUUUCAUAAAGCAUUAUUUAGAAUUGGGCUUCUAAGAGAGCUCACCUUAUUUUUUUCUGCAUUUUGAAGCACUCUGGGCAUGAAGUAUGCUGUACUUAAGCAUUUGUCCUUGCAAGUAAUGAAUGAUAACGAGACAAACCAGACUUUGAGCUGAGUUAGUGAGUGUGAUGUGUGUUGAUUCUAUGAAGCUCAUUUAAACAAAUGCCCUGUUUGGUGCAGGAUCAGGUCAGAAAAUCUUUCGCUGCCCAAGGGAUCCAGUUUUAACCUCAAUUAGAAAAACUGGCACAAGACCAUUUCUAGGGCCAUUUUGCAUGUCUGCCACUUCCCUUUGGGACCUCUGUUUGGGGGAGAACGUUCUUGGUUUUUGUGCUUCUGCCCUGGUUCUUAAGGUCACUAGCUCUGUGGGCAAAUCUGUGCUUUCUGUGCCUAGGUUUCCUCUUCUGUGAGGAGAUAAGAGUUCCUGACAACAUUGCUGAGUGGGUUGAGCAUUUGAAGCCCUCAGCAGGGUGUCUGGCAUAUGAAAAGGCCUCUAUUGCCAUUGCUUGUGGUGAGGAGGAGGACAAUGAUGACAAUGUGACAUAGACAACCCAUUGCUGGGUCCAUGCCUAUCAUACAGUAGGCAGCACAGAAUGGGGGACCCCAGUCCUGCUCUGACCACUGUGUCCUGUUCCUUCCUACCUUUGGGUCCUCCAUGAAUCCAUAAGCAUGCUCUCUGUCCAUCAACAAAAACAUACUGAGUGUCCAUGAAAGGCAUUACUGAAGAGACCCAGAGAGAGACAGGCUGACAGUAGUAGUUUGUUUUUUGUUUUUUGUUUUGAGACAGAGUUUCGCUCUUAUCACCCAGGCUGGAGUGCAAUGGUGCGAUCUCAGCCCACUUUAACCUCCGUCUCCUAGGUUCAAGCGAUUCUCCUGCCUCAGCCUCCCCAGUAGCUGGGAUUACAGGUGCCCGCCACCACGCCCAGCUAAUUUUUGUAUUUUUAGUAGAGAUGAGGUUUCACCCUGUUGGCCAGGCUGGUCUUGAACUCCUGAGUUCAGGUGAUCCAUCUGCCUCGGCUUCCCAGAGUGCUCGGAUUACAGGUGUGAGCCACCACGUCCGGCCAAUAGUUUUAUGUAAAGCAAGGUUUUAAAACUUUUUUGUUCCAUUGGAACCAUUUGACAGUAUGAGAACUCCUCCAAGAACCCUAGCAUAUAAAUCAUAAUAAAAGAUGAGAUGCCCUGGUUGAAAUUGGAAUACCUUUUGGCCUAAAGACAGGCAUCCUGGAACCAGGCAGGGGUUGACCGCUUGUGGUAUCCCCACCAAGCCUCGUAUCCUGGGAUCUGGGAUCUGAUUUUCAACUGGGAAGACUAGAGACUUGUGAUAUGACCUUGAGGACUGACUAACCUUCUCCCCAAACCUCCCCAAAUGAACAUGUGAUGGAGACCAUGCCCACAGUACCAGCUUGUACAUAAGCAGUGAAAACUGGAACUGGUACUCAGUCUAUCCAUGUAAUUAAGCCACAGGGGCAGCAAGCACCAAACCUGUAGGCUGCCUGGUGGGAGUGGAGUUCAAAAUACUUGUUGGAGCAAGUACGAUGCUGUCAUUAGCCUGUUGCAUCCAUUUCAUCACUGGGGUAUCUUGACACUGUGUUUAGAAAUACAAGUCCUUGUGUCCCCAGCAUGCAUCUUCCUUUGAGGGAUAGUGACUUACGGACUCGGCUGGGUACUGUGCAGCUUUGCCUCUUGAUGCCUUCUUUUCCUGUGAUUCUCGAAUGGCCAACCCCCCCAAGUGGACCACUUUAUUGCUUCAGCUGGUGGUGAUGCCUCCAUGGCGCGGGUGUCCUGAUUCCACAGCAGGAGACCUGAGCCUGCCAUACUGAGUCUAUGGACAGUUCCACAGCAAUGAAUCAAUGCAGCUGUAGAGGAAUGGAAGAAAACAAGGAAAGGCCUAAACGGCAGCGGCAAAACAACUUUCCCAUGUUUCCCUCUCCUAAAGCCUGGAAUUUCAGAGGGCGAAAACGGAAACAGAGCACCCAAGAUGAAGAUGCUGUUAGCCUUUGCAGUCUCGACAUAAGUGAGCCUAGUAAUAAACGGGUCAAACCCCUUUCCCGAGUCACGUCGCUAGCAAACCUCAUCCCGCCCGUGAAGGCCACGCCAUUAAAGCGCUUCAGUCAAACCCUGCAGCGCUCCAUUAGCUUCCGCAGUGAGAGCCGCCCUGACAUCCUCGCCCCCCGACCCUGGUCCAGAAAUGCCGCCCCCUCGAGCACGAAACGGAGAGAUAGCAAGCUGUGGAGUGAGACCUUCGAUGUGUGCGUCAAUCAGAUGCUUACAUCCAAGGAAAUCAAACGUCAGGAGGCGAUCUUUGAGCUUUCCCAAGGAGAAGAAGACUUGAUAGAAGACUUGAAAUUAGCAAAAAAGGCCUAUCAUGACCCCAUGCUGAAACUCUCCAUAAUGACAGAACAAGAGUUGAAUCAAAUUUUUGGAACACUGGACUCUCUAAUUCCUCUACAUGAAGAGCUCCUUAGUCAGCUUCGAGAUGUUAGGAAGCCUGAUGGCUCGACUGAACAUGUUGGUCCCAUCCUCGUGGGCUGGCUCCCUUGCCUCAGCUCCUAUGAUAGCUACUGCAGCAAUCAAGUAGCCGCCAAAGCUCUGCUGGACCACAAAAAGCAAGAUCACCGAGUCCAGGAUUUCCUACAGCGAUGUUUAGAAUCCCCCUUUAGCCGCAAACUAGAUCUCUGGAAUUUCCUCGAUAUUCCAAGAAGCCGCCUGGUAAAAUACCCUCUGCUUCUCCGAGAAAUCUUGAGGCACACACCAAAUGAUAAUCCAGAUCAGCAGCACUUGGAAGAAGCUAUAAAUAUCAUUCAGGGAAUUGUGGCAGAAAUCAACACCAAGACUGGUGAAUCUGAAUGCCGCUAUUAUAAAGAGCGGCUUCUUUACUUGGAAGAAGGCCAGAAAGACUCCCUGAUCGACAGCUCUCGAGUCUUGUGUUGUCAUGGUGAACUGAAGAACAAUCGGGGCGUGAAACUGCAUGUUUUCCUGUUCCAAGAAGUGCUUGUGAUCACUCGAGCCGUCACCCACAAUGAGCAGCUUUGCUACCAGCUGUACCGUCAGCCAAUCCCCGUGAAAGACCUCCUGCUGGAAGACCUCCAGGAUGGAGAAGUGAGGCUGGGUGGCUCCCUGCGAGGGGCAUUCAGCAACAAUGAGAGAAUUAAAAACUUCUUCAGAGUCAGUUUCAAAAAUGGAUCCCAAAGUCAGACCCACUCGCUACAAGCCAAUGACACUUUCAACAAACAGCAGUGGCUUAACUGUAUUCGUCAAGCCAAAGAAACAGUUUUGUGUGCUGCCGGGCAAGCUGGGGUGCUUGACUCCGAGGGAUCGUUCCUAAAUCCCACCACCGGGAGCAGAGAGCUACAGGGAGAAACAAAACUUGAGCAGAUGGACCAAUCGGACAGUGAGUCAGACUGUAGUAUGGACACGAGUGAGGUCAGCCUCGACUGUGAGCGCAUGGAACAGACAGACUCUUCCUGUGGAAACAGCAGGCACGGUGAAAGUAACGUCUGACAGAAGCAUGUGCACUUCGGGAAGCAGGCCUGCAUCUUACCUGUACAGUAUUUGCAUUCCACAGAUGGAACGGUUUGGAGAAGCACUUUUUCAUACUUUUGUGAAAGUAUACAUGUUGGCCCAGUCUCUCGUAUCUGUACCUUUGUCCCUAGUACUGUAACUGCCAAUCUGUCUGUGUAAGCUGGAAUCUGUGGCAACUAUUACCCUGUGUUGUAUUUCCCAAGUGUCUGGAUGGAUGGAGAGGUACUCAAACAAGUUACUUUCAGUUGUCCUGCUGGAUUUUAAAAAAAUAGAAAAAGAAUCUCAAAACUACUGUUUUACAUAGAUUGUUUGAAGAGUCCUUCCUCUUGUGCUUCUGUACCACUUUCCCAGCUCUUAGAUGUGGUAGCUAAAGGCACGGAAUUUAGACGGCCUUGUAAAUAGGGCAUGAGGAACUCAUCUGUGUAUUGGGAUGGUAUUAGAGAGAGAAUCAGGAAAGACCAACUCAUGAAGUGAACUUGGUUUGAUCUUACUCAACUAGAAAGCUUGAAAACAUCCCUGGGGAUUCUGAAGGCUUAAUUUUGCAAAGGAGGAUGCAUUGUCUGAACUUUGCAACUUCAUCCAGUGCAAGUUUGAUGCAAGAAUGUAUUAGGACAUAAAAUAGAGGCUGACCUUAAAAGGGCCAGGACAGAAGCGGCUGCCAGCUCUGAAUCUUUAACUGAAAUGCACAUGGCACCAGGAGGUGUCUCUCAUAGUUGGUUGCUAGCCUAAAACAUCAGAAUAGAACCCAAAGGGCUUAGGAAGGCCUGCCAGGAUAACAAGAAGGCCCUGUAUUCAUUGUGUUUCAUCUGCCUAGGCCUACUCAUUAUUUUAGAGAAUGAAUGAAGCAACAAGGAAGAGAGACCAUGACUCUAUCGAUGACACUGUUUAUAGAAACACAGGAGAGGAAGAAUUUGGAAUGAAAAGCACUUCGUCAGAACCUUCUGUGGGAGCCAUUGAGAGAAAAGCAUGGUCCAGUGCCUUCUGAGAAAGGCCAGAGCUUUGGGCUUUCCUGCUCUGCUUUUGGGUCGUCAAUUUGCCAUCUCUGGUUCUGUGCUAUAAUCAGAAUUGUAAUUAUGUUCUCCAGAGGCCAAUUUCAUUAACUCUGAUUAAUUAGAAUCAGCUAGCCAGAUUAGUAACCUCUUUGUCCAGCCUUGAUUUACAGUGCAGGGUAAAGUGCAGACCUUAAAAACAGCUAAGUACCUAGAAGAGCUCCCUGCAAGUGUAAAUAUUAAGGAUGACCUGUGCAAAAUUAUACCCACACCAGCACUAGUGGUAAUUAUUCUAAAUUAUUGCCAAAAAGUUUUUUUUAAUCUGUCUUUCAAGUUUACAGAAAAGAAAGCAGUAAAUGCAUUGAUGUCAUUUUAUUAUGUACAUAUAUCAUGUGCAUUCAAGCUGUGUGACAAGAUAUAUCAAUAUAAAAACAAGGUAUAUACUUUAUUAUUUUUUGAAAACAAGGAUAUUGUGAUCAAUUUUACCCUGUAAAACAUAUUUCUGUAUUUAUAGGUCUUAAACAUGAUGAAUUUUUUCUAUUACAAGUUUAUUUAAAACUGCUUUCUCAAGUCGUUAUUGAUACAGCAAGUGAACCUGCUGCAGACAGAAGCAGAGGAAAGCCAAGAACAGCCUUUAUUGGUGAAGAAAAGAAUGAAUGAUUCUUUGUAGGCGCCAUCAGCCACUUUUAGAAGCCAUCAGCCAGUGUGUUGGGAAAAGAGGUUUGUCAAGUGUUGGCCUAUGGGAAGGUGGUCAAUGAAUGUUUUGAUGAAAUGAAUGUUUUUGUAUAAUGGCCUUAAACUUUUCUGGAAGUAUUUCAAAUAAAUUACAUUAUUAAGUCA